GGGACGCUUUGAGCCGCCCCGAACUAAGCAGGGCGGUCGGGGCUCUGCCCAGGAAACGGGGCAGGAAUGGCCUCUCCGUCUUCCAGAUGCGUGCGCUGAGGCCUGGAGGGGCGAAGAGCCUCUCGCACCUGGGAGUAGUGGGACCCAGCCUCCUGCCUCUGUUGCUGCUCUUUUCCAAAACAGCACUUCCUUGGCGCCUUUCCUCUACACCGUUUUCCAGGAGUCAUACUCCAUGGGUUUAUGUGAUAAAUGAUCUUGGCAUAGAAGAGAAUUUAAAGAAUGAUGGAAAACCUAAAUGUCAAACUGGUGGAAAAUCUAAGAGGACCAUUCAAGGCACUCAUAAAACUACUAAACAGAGUACUGCAGUGGACUGUAAAAUAACAUCGUCUACGACUGGAGAUAAACACUUUGAUAAAAGUCCCACUAAAACAAGGCACCCUCGGAAAAUUGAUCUAAGAGCUCGAUACUGGGCAUUUCUUUUUGAUAAUCUUCGCCGAGCAGUAGAUGAAAUCUAUGUAACUUGCGAAUCAGAUCAGAGUGUGGUCGAAUGUAAGGAGGUGCUAAUGAUGCUGGAUAACUAUGUAAGAGAUUUCAAAGCAUUGAUUGACUGGAUUCAGCUUCAGGAAAAGCUAGAGAAGACAGAUGCUCAAAGCAGACCAACAUCAUUGGCAUGGGAAGUAAAGAAGAUGUCUCCGGGACGCCAUGUGAUUCCAAGUCCAUCAACAGAUAGAAUAAAUGUAACAUCAAAUGCUCGACGAAGCUUAAAUUUUGGAGGUUCAACUGGCACAGUGCCAGCUCCUCGUCUGGCUCCCACAGGUGUCAGUUGGGCUGACAAGGUAAAGGCUCAUCAUACAGGCUCUACUGCUUCUUCAGAAAUAACACCCGCCCAGUCUUGCCCACCAAUGACAGUGCAGAAGGCCUCACGCAAAAAUGAACGGAAAGAUGCUGAAGGAUGGGAGACCGUUCAGAGAGGAAGGCCUAUUCGUUCUCGAUCAACAGCAGUGAUGCCAAAAGUUUCAUUGGCAACAGAAGCCACAAGAUCAAAGGAUGACAGUGAUAAAGAAAAUGUAUGUCUUUUACCUGAUGAAAGCAUACAGAAAGGUCAAUUUGUUGGAGAUGGAACUUCUAAUACUAUAGAAUCUCAUCCCAAAGACUCAUUACACUCUUGUGACCAUCCUCUUGCCGAAAAAACCCAGUUCACAGUGAGUACAUUGGAUGAUGUGAAGAAUUCUGGCAGUAUUCGAGACAAUUAUGUUCGAACUUCUGAAAUAUCUGCUGUCCACAUUGAUACAGAGUGUGUUUCAGUUAUGCUGCAAGCUGGUACACCUCCUUUACAAGUAAAUGAAGAAAAAUUUCCAGCAGAGAAAGCAAGGAUAGAAAAUGAAAUGGACCCUUCAGAUAUUUCAAAUGUGAGUGCUGCUAACUUGUCCAUGGCAGAAGUCCUUGCUAAAAAAGAAGAGCUAGCAGAUCGUCUAGAAAAGGCCAAUGAAGAAGCCAUUGCUAGUGCUAUUGCUGAAGAAGAACAGUUAACUAGAGAAAUUGAAGCUGAAGAAAACAAUGAUAUUAACAUUGAAACUGACAACGACAGUGAUUUUUCUGCCAGCAUGGGCAGUGGGAGUGUUUCUUUCUGUGGUAUGUCCAUGGACUGGAACGAUGUCCUUGCAGAUUAUGAAGCUCGUGAGUCUUGGCGCCAAAAUACAUCCUGGGGGGACAUUGUAGAAGAAGAACCUGCUAGACCUCCAGGGCAUGGAAUUCACAUGCAUGAAAAACUUUCUUCACCCUCUCGUAAAAGAACAAUUGCAGAAUCUAAGAAGAAACAUGAAGAAAAACAAAUGAAAGCACAGCAGCUAAGGGAAAAGUUACGCGAAGAGAAAACAUUGAAGCUUCAGAAAUUGUUAGAAAGGGAGAAGGAUGUCCGGAAGUGGAAGGAAGAAUUGCUAGAUCAACGACGCAGGAUGAUGGAAGAAAAAUUACUUCAUGCUGAGUUUAAGCGAGAAGUGCAGUUACAAGCAAUUGUGAAAAAAGCACAAGAAGAAGAAGCUAAGGUAAAUGAAAUUGCCUUUAUAAAUACCCUUGAAGCCCAGAAUAAACGUCAUGAUGUUUUAUCAAAAUUGAAGGAAUAUGAACAGAGGCUUAAUGAGCUACAGGAAGAGCGUCAGAGAAGACAGGAAGAAAAGCAAGCACGUGAUGAAGCUGUGCAGGAACGCAAGAGAGCUCUAGAGGCAGAGCGGCAGGCCCGUGUAGAAGAAUUGUUAAUGAAGAGGAAAGAACAAGAAGCCCGAAUUGAACAACAGAGGCAAGAAAAGGAAAAAGCCCGUGAGGAUGCAGCCCGGGAAAGAGCUAGAGACAGGGAAGAACGAUUGGCAGCACUCACAGCUGCUCAACAAGAAGCUAUGGAAGAGUUACAGAAAAAAAUUCAGCUCAAGCAUGAUGAAAGUAUUCGAAGGCACAUGGAACAGAUUGAACAAAGAAAAGAAAAAGCUGCUGAGCUAAGCAGUGGGCGACAUGCAAAUACUGAUUAUGCCCCCAAACUGACCCCUUAUGAAAGAAAGAAGCAGUGUUCUCUCUGCAAUGUCCUGAUCUCUUCAGAGGUAUAUCUUUUUAGCCAUGUUAAAGGGAGAAAACACCAGCAAGCCGUGAGAGAGAAUACCAGCAUCCAGGGGCGUGAACUGUCAGAUGAAGAAGUGGAGCAUCUUUCCUUGAAGAAGUACAUUAUUGACAUUGUGGUUGAAAGUACAGCUCCAGCAGAAGCUUUGAAAGAUGGAGAAGAGCGGCAAAAAAAUAAAAAAAAAGCCAAAAAGAUAAAAGCCCGGAUGAACUUCAGGGCUAAGGAAUAUGAGAGUUUAAUGGAAACCAAAAAUUCUGGCUCUGAUUCACCUUAUAAAGCAAAGCUUCAGCGAUUAGCCAAAGAUCUUCUAAAACAAGUACAAGUUCAAGACAGUGGCUCAUGGGCAAACAAUAAAGUGUCUGCUUUGGAUCGGACCCUAGGAGAGAUCACUAGAAUACUGGAAAAAGAGAAUGUGGCAGAUCAGAUUGCAUUUCAAGCUGCUGGUGGAUUAACAGCCCUUGAACACAUCCUUCAAGCAGUAGUCCCAGCCACAAAUGUGAACACAGUUUUAAGAAUUCCUCCUAAGUCUCUCUGCAAUGCAAUCAAUGUUUACAACCUCACCUGCAAUAACUGUUCAGAAAACUGCAGUGAUGUUCUGUUUAGUAACAAGAUUACCUUCUUAAUGGACCUCCUGAUACACCAGUUGACGAUGAGGAAACUUGAGUCCCAGAGAGGUUGACUUGCCCAAGGCUACAUAGAUAUUAAGUCAGAAAGCCAAGAAUCAGACCUAGGUGUAUCAUACCCAAGUUGGGGGACAUUCUGCACAAUAACUGACUAAUAUUUUUCAAAAACGUCAAUAUCAUGAAAGACAAGGAAAAAGUGAGGAACUGUCACAGAAUGGAGGAGACUAAGGACACAUAACAAUUAAAUGUAAUGUAUGAUCCUGGACCAGAAAAAGGACAUCAAUGGGAAAACUUGGAAAUUCAAGUAAGAUCUAUAGAAUAGUCUGUUUUAUUGGCUCAAUGUUAAUUUCCUCCUUUCAAUUAUUAUACUAUGUUUUUGUAAGAUGUUAACAGUAAGGGACACUGGGUUAAAGGAAUGCUCUAUUUUUGCAACAUAUUUGUUUACUUAAAAUUAUUUCAAAACAAGAAUGAAAAAAAAUAACUUCAUGCUCUCCUAUCAUUUCAUACUGCAUCAUCUGGAAGAAUUUACUCCAUGAAGCUUAUUCUAUGUUGGUAGUGGAAUAAGAGACAUUACUUUGAACAGAACAAGUAAUGAAAGAGAAUGGCAUUUGAAAUGUGAGGGAAUGAACAAGAAGACUUAAAGAAAGAAUCUUGGUUCUGCAUAUGUAUAGAUGUCAUAUGUCAUAAUAUAGAUGACAUAUUGUCUCAGUCCAGGCUGCAAUUACAAAAUACCAUAGACUGGAUGGCUUAUAAACACAGUAAUUUAUUUCUCACAUUCUGUAGUCUGGAAGUUCAAGAUCAAAGUACCACCAUAGGUUAUGGUGAGGGCCCUCUUCCAGGUUUCAAACUGCUGACUUGUCACUUUAUCCCCAGAUGGUGAAAAGAGUGCAAGCUAAUUCUCUGGCCUCUUUUUAUAAGGGCACUAAUCCCAUUCAUGAGGAUUCCAUCCUUAUGACCAAAUUACCUCCCACAGGCCCCGUCUCCAGAUAUCACCACAUUAAACAUUAUAUUUCAACAUGUGAAUUUAGGAGGGACACAGCAUUCGGACCCUAGUACAUACAGUAAAUGAUAUGAUAGCAGCCUGUAUAGAGUACUAUGGGAGCACAGAGAAAGAUAUUCAGUGAUCCUCCCUGAGACAUCACAAAAGAGGGACAUUUGAGUUAGUUCUCAGCUCCUCAUAAUAGCUCUCAUUUAUUAAGUACCAACCAUGGGCCUGGAGCUUGUGGGUACCUUGAUCAUUUUCUUCUUCUUUGAAAGCCUAGUUCCCUUUGAAUAAUAAAGCCCUAGUUCCCUUUGAAUAACCUUCGUUGUAACCUAAGGUUUCUUGACCUCAGAAAAGCUUUUAAUCUCUCAAUGGAUUUGACCACAUUCUAUGUUUAUUCUGCCCAUGAAUUUUGCUUAGUUUGGAACUGGGAUCCUGGGACAUUAGUUUGCCAAACACAUUUGAACCUUUUUUUUCUUAUACAUGGCACUUUCUGAGUUUUUUCAUUCCUUUUGGGCUCUUUAUUUUAUCGCUGUCAAUUCUUACUGUUGCUGUAACUGGGUUUGUGGCAGUGAGUGAAGGAGGAAGUGUUUCCUGGUUUGGGGUGGUUGGUGAUGGUGAUUUUUAUGUUUCUGAAAAUCACUUGAGUGUAUUUUCAUUUUUCUUGCUAACUGGUUUUGAUGUACAUGUAACUGAAAUAUGGACCACUGACUUAUUAGUAUCCUUUAAAUAAGGGAUUAAAAAAUAGUUGUCAAUACAUUUUCCAACAAGAAUAGAAAAAAGCAUAAAAGAAGCUAAUUAAUUGUGAUCUGGUGUUAUUUAUAAGACAACUGAUUAUCAUCAGGUACUGUUGUCUUUCUGGUUAUGUUUAGCAAACCCAGAUGGUUUAGGAGACAUUUUUCUUCUAGCCACUUGGAGUUUGUUUUGGCACUCUUGUAUUUCAUUUUAAUUACUAUUUCCAAAGCAUUGUCCAGAUGCCUGGGUUACAGAGGUGAACUGGACACAGUUCCAUCACUCUAGAAGCACACAGUUAAGGAAGGAAGAAAUUGCAUAUGCAAAUAUUAAUGACUAUAGGAAGGGAUGAGAAGUUCUAUAAUGUUAUCAGAACUACAACGUAGCUCAGACAACCUAGUAGAGUACCUAGCACAUAAUAGGUGCUUGUUCAGUAUUUGAUGAAUGAAUGAAUAAAUUCUGACUUGGGGAAUUGGGAAGAUUUGAGGGAAGAAGUUUAAUUCGAUCAUACCUUGAAUACUUUGAACCAAGGAGUUCAAAGCUACAGUGGGCCAUGAUUGUGCCACUGCACUGCAGUCUCAGCAACAGAGUGAGAUCCUGUCUUUAAAAAAAAAAAAAAAAGACACCCCAACUCUCAGCUUCUCCUCUGGGAGGGAGAGAGAAGAGUGGGGCAUGUGGACAAUAUCCCAGCUUUUUGGAAGGCUGCCUGAGAGAUUGCUAUCUGUCUUGCCUGACUUGGGGCUAGCAUACUUUGGAUGCUGCUGAGAACAACAAAAACAGGGAGGCUUGCUGCCAUAAAACUAGAGAACGUGCAAUGUGUAUUAGUCUGUUUUCACACUACUAUAAAGAACUCCCUGAGACUGGGUAAUUUAUAAAGAAAGAGGUUUAAUUGACUCACAGUUCUGCAGGCUGUACAGUCCUUGAGAAACUUACAAUCAUGGCAGAAGACAAAGGGGAAGCAGGUACAUUUUACAUGGCUGGAGAAGGAGGAGGAGAGUGAAGGAGGAGAUGCUACACACUUUUAAACAACUGAUCUUGUAAAAACUCACUAUCACAAGAACAGCAAGGGGGAAAUCUGCCUCCAUGAUCCAGUCACCUCCCACCAGGCCCUUCCUCCAACAUUGAAGGUUACAAUUCAACAUGACAUCUGGGCAGGGACGCAAAUCCAAACCAUAUCACAGUGCUAAAGACAGAUACCAGAGAAAGGAAGAGAUUAUGAUCACUUGAAUAAGAAAGCAGCAAGCAUCUCUAGUUGAGAAAUUGCAUACAUUGGCCUAGAGAAGUUGUAUCCCCCCCAAAGUUUUCAGAGGCCCCCAGAACCCCUAGCUGAGCUCAUUAGUGAGGGUUUUCCAUACUACAAAAGCCAGUUCAUAAAGACUGGAAGAAGUGGCUUUUUUUGUCAAGUGCACAGAUCCCAACAAAGCUUUCGAGACGUAGAAGAAACAGGGAAACAUGGCCCAAAGAAAGGAGCAAAAUAAAUCUUCACAAACCAAUCCUAAAGAAACAAAGACAUGAAUUACCUGACAAAGAAUUCAAAAUAGCCCUCAUAAAGAUGCUGUAUGAGCUCAAGGUAACAAUGCAUGAGCAAAAUGAGAAUAUCAACAAAGAGACAGAAAAUACAAAAAAAAAAAAAAAAAAAAAAAGAAGAACCAACCAAUUUUGGAACUGAAGAAUACAAUAGCUACACUGAAAAAUUCACAAUAGGGGUUCAACAGCAGACUCAGUCAAGCAGAAGAGAGAAACAGCAAACUCAAGACAAGUUAUUUGACAUUAUCCACCCAGAGGAACAAAAAGAAAAAGAAUGAGAAAGAGUGAUGAAAGCCUAAGGGAUUUGUGGCAUACCAUCAAGCCAACCCAUUAUACACAUUAUGGAAAGUUCACAAGAAGAAGAGAGAAAGGAAUGGGCAGAAAGUUUACUUAAAUAGUGACCCAAAACUUCCCAAAUCUGGGAAAGAAAAUGGACAUCCAGAUUCAAGAAGACUAAAGGACCCCAAAUAAGAUCAACAUAAACACACACCAAGACACAUUAUAAUAAAAUUGUCAAACUCUCAAAGACAGUAAGAGAAUUUUGAAAACAAGAAAAAAGUGACUUGUCGUGUACUAGGGAACACACAUCAGACUAUCAACAUAUUUCUCAGCAGAAACCCUGUAGGCCAGAAGGGAGUGGAGGGAUAUAUUCAAAGGGCCAAUUAACUGAUCUUUGACAAGAUUGCCAGGAAUACACAGCAGAAAAAAGGUAGUCUUCAAUAAACUGUGUUGGAAAAACUGGAUAUCCACAUGCAAAAGAAUGAUAUGGGACCCUUAUCUUAUACCAUACACAAAAAUAAACUCAAAAUUGAUUAAACACUUAAAUGUAAGACUUGAACUAAAAAAACUCCAAAUUAAAACAUAGGGGAAAACCUUCAUAACAUUGAUCUUGACUGUGAUUUAUCAGAUAUGACACCAAAGCAGGGGCAACAAAAGCCAAAAAUAGAUAAAUGAGAUUACAUUAAACUAAAAAGCUUCCGCAUCAGAGUCACAAUCAACAGUGCAGAAAGGCAAUGUACAGAAUGAAAGAAAAUAUUUGUAAACCGUAUGUCUGAUAAAGGGGUGCUGUGGGCUGAAUGUUUGUAUCCCCAGAAUUAGUAUGUUGAAACCUAAUCACCACUGUGAUGGCAUUAGGAGGAGGAGCCUUUGAAAGGUGAUUCCAUCAUGAGGACAAAGCCCUCAUGAAUACUUUCAGAACCCUUAUAAAAGAUGCCCCAGAGAGCUGCCUUGCCCCUUCUGUCAGGUGAGGUCACAGCUGGAAAGCGCCUUCUAUGAACCAGAAAGCACCACUUCUGCCAGCAUCUUGAUCUCAGGACUUCCUAACUUCCUGAACUGUGAGAAAUAAAUUUCUGUUUGUUGUUUAUAACAGUAUUUUGUUAUAGCAGCUCAAAUGGAAUAAGUCAGACGUUAAUAUCCAAAUAUAUAAAGAACUACAACUCAAUAGCAAAAAUAUAUGAUAAUCAAUUAAAAAUGAGAAAAGGGCUUAAAUAGACAUUUCUUCAAAGAAAAUACACAGUUGAACAACACGUAUAUGAAAAGAUGACCAAAAUCACUAAUCACUGUGAAAAUGCAAAUCAAAACCACAAUGAGAUAUCACCUCAUGCCUGUUAGGAUGGCUGUUAUAAAACAAAUCAGAAAAUAAGUAUUGGUAGGAGUGUGGUGAAAUUGGAAAUGUUGUGCACUUUUGGUGCAGGCACUAAGGAAAAAAGUAUGGAAGUUCCUAAAAAAAAUUAAAAAGAGAACUACCAUAUGAUUCAUCAAUCCUGCUUCUGGGUACGUAUUCAAAAUAAUUAAAAUUGGGAUCUUGAAUAGAUAUCUGCACUGCCAUGUUCACCUCGGCAUUAUUCACAAGAGCCAAGAGGUGGAAAUACCUAAAUAUUCAUCAACAAAUGAGUGGAUAAAGAAAACGUGGCAUAUACAAUUGACUCUUAAACACUACAAGUUUGAACUGCAUAGGUCUAUUUAUGCAUAGUUUUUUUUUCAACCAAACAUGGAUCAAAAAUGCAGUCUCCAUGGGAUACAAAACCCACACAUAUGUAGGACUGACUUUUCAUAUAUGCAGCUUCCACAGAGCUGACUGCAGGACUUGAGAAUAUGCAGAUUUGGGUAUACACAGGGAGCACUGAACCAAUCGCCUGUGUAUACUGAGGGACAACUGUACAAACAAUGGAAUAUUAAUCAACCUUAAAAAAGAAGGGAAUUCUGUCAUAUGCUAUAAUGUAUAAACCUUGAUGAUGCUAUAAGUGAAAUAAGCCAAUUACAAAAACAGAAAUACUGCAUGAUUCUACUUAAAUGACAUAUCUAAAAGAAUCAGCCUCAUAGAAACAAAGUAGAAUGGUGGUUGCCAGGGACCAAGGGGAGGGGGAAGCAGAGUUGUUUAAUAGGUUUAGCGUUUCAGUCAAGUGAGAUGAAAAAGUUCUAGAGACCCAUUUUACAACAAUGUGCAUAUAGUUAACAAUAUUGUAAUAUGCACCUAAAAAUUGAUAAAGAAAAUUUAUAUGUCUUUUUACAAAAAAAAAAAAAAAAAAGACCAGUGAAAGUACUACUGAGUGCUGUGAAAAUAGAUGGAUAAGCUUUUAAUGUUGGGCAAGAUCUAAACAGUCCAAUAUACUGAUGAGCAAAUUGAGAUGUGGAAAAGGAUCACAGAGCUACCUAGUGGCAGAACCAUGACCUGGACCCUGGUCUUCUGAGUCCCUGACCAGGACUUCCCUUCCUAUAAGCUAAAUUGAUGUGUCCUCAUUUUCUUAAGUUGACAAAUGAAACAAAGCAACAAUUUUGUGACUUUAAUUUUAUAAGUUUAAUAGUAUUACUUUGGUAAGAUAUACUGAAAAAGCACUUAAUUAAAAGAUUUAUAAUUUCUUGAUGUUUCAUUGCAUUUUAAAAGGCAUUAAAUAUUUUAUUAGCAGUCUUAUUUUUAAUUCAUAGUGACCUGUUCCUUAUGAAAUAUUUAAUGAAUAUGCUGAUAAAUUGUGUGUAUGUAUUUUUGGGAGCCAAGGAGAUUGUUAAUUGAAAAGUGAUGUACUAACCUUAAAUAAUUGAUAUGAUACUGUUGAAUCAGAGAGGCUGCUGGUGAGCUCUUCAGAAGGUGACAAGAAAGCCCUGGAUACAAACAAAGGAAAUCUAAGUGCAACCUUACAGCAAGGGGAUUGUUUUUCACUUAGUCAUGUGCAGAGCCAUCCAGGUGCCUGUUGAUUUUCAUUACAGCAGCAAGGCCUGGAACUCUCCAUUCACCACAUUGUUUCUUUAUAUUGAGUUGCCAGAACAUAGACUCCAUAGUUAAUUACAUGGGAGCAAAAAUCCCUCAACACUACAGGUAACAGUACUCUUCCAGUUGCAUCUUGUUUCCUUCUUUCCUCACUAUAUAGUACGGUACUUGCUCAGCAUAUCUAGGACACGUUGCCUUUUCCUUCAGCAGAAGUGUGAACUCUGUUUAUGUCUCCUGUGCCAUAUGUCUUAUUGACACAGAAUUUCAAAACUGGAGAGGAGGUCUUCAUAGUAUGUAGUCUAUUUCAGUCCACUCGUUUUAUAGAUGAGGAUAAUGGACUUCAAAAGAGGAGAGGGAUGGGAGAUAUGUGGGGUUGGAUACUUGCCCAAGUUCUACAGCCUGUUAACACUAUAACUGGGAUGCAAAUUCAGGUCUCCUAAAUCCUAAGUUAACUUUCUAUUAUUUUACUUAACGGACUGCCCAUUUUUAAAGUUGGUGAGAACAGUUAAGGGAUGUUGUGUGUAUAGAGCUUUACUCUCAAAGCUACAUUCAGAAUUCAGCUGGUAAAAGAACAUGGGCCAGAUUUUAACUCAGAUUGCCUUUCUACUACAUUCAUAUGAAAUAGUAUCCUCACCACCAUUAUCACUAUCACCUAAAAUAAUUAAAUGACUACUUGAGGGAGAAGCUGACACUUGUACCUUCAUCAGUGUAAAAAAUAUGUCACACUGCUUACAAAUACUGAUAGAUAAAGCAAACAAAAUUAUUAAAGGUGUAAAAGGUUUCAGUAAAACAAUUAACAGUUUAAUGCACAUAGAAUCCUAUGUACAACAUUAGAGAAUAUAUAUUCUCUAUAAGCACAUAUGGAAGAUGUAUAAGAAUUAUUCACUAAGCCAUAAGCAAGUAUUAUCAAAUUUGAAAGAAUCCACAUCAUAGAAGAUGACCCAGUUCUGCUUCAGUUAUGGAUGAAUAAGCUCCUAUCGGACUGACCCUCCUGCAGACAACAAAUGUAAAUGCUGAGUAAAGUAUGUGAAAACAAAUACCUGAAAAGUACUAAGGACCAAUGAAAAGCAGAUCCUGAUGGGAAUAGUCACUUGGAAGAAAGGAACAGCGUUGGGUAAGUUUCCUGGUUGUAUGGCUUUCAGCAUGAGGGCAGGCUACAGUUGGUGCCACAUGGGCUGGCUAGAACUCAAUAGAAAAUCCACAAUCUUUUUAUCCUGAAGAACCAGAGGACAGAAUUCAGGGCAAAGACAAGUGCUAGAAUGUUAGGAGGAUAUUCAGGAGGAGAAAAGCUACAAAGGGAUAUCCCCUAAGUAUUUACAAAUACCUGCAUGAUUCUGAAUAUACUGUACAUGUAUGAGACAACUCCGUAUAACUCAGCUAAAGACAAGAAAACUGGGAUUUGAGCUGCUAUUCACUAGUAGAGUUUUGCAGUUUGAGUCCAACAAAGUCAAAUGGCUACUUUAAAAAGAAAAUAUCAACACCUGUAAGAGAAAUAUAGCAGAAUCCAGAUUCUUCAUGACAUAGCAUUCACAGUGUUUGGGAUUUCUUGACAUAAAGAGAAAGAAGAUGUGCAUUAUUUUCAAGAGUUAAGGCAAUUAACAGAGGCCAAUCCUGAGAUGACACAGAUGUUAGAAUUAGCAAACAAGGAUAUUAAAACAACUUUAUGACUCAGCUCAAUGACAGAAAGAAAAAUGUGCUGAUAAUGAAGGAUAUGAAAUAUCACAGAAGUAAAAACAUAAUAAAGAAUCAAACAGAAAUUUAAAAACUAGAAAAUACAAUACCUGAAAUAAAAAACUUACUAUAUGAAUUAAUAAAUGAGAAAGAAUGAUGAAAAA